GUAGAGGGACAGUGGAUAGGUGCCCGAGGCCUACAGCUGGCCUGGGGCUCGUGUCUGGGCUUCGGACGUUGGGGCCCGGUGGCCCACCCUUUCCGUAGUUGUCCCAAAUGGAGCUGGAAUUGGAUGCUGGUGACCAAGACCUGCUGGCCUUCCUGCUAGAGGAAAGUGGAGAUUUGGGGACGGCACCCGAUGAGGCCGUGAGGGCCCCACUGGACUGGGCGCUGCCGCUUUCUGAGGUACCGAGCGACUGGGAAGUAGAUGAUUUGCUGUGCUCCCUGCUGAGUCCCCCAGCGUCGUUGAACAUUCUCAGCUCCUCCAACCCCUGCCUUGUCCACCAUGACCACACCUACUCCCUCCCACGGGAAACUGUCUCUAUGGAUCUAGAGAGUGAGAGCUGUAGAAAAGAGGGGACCCAGAUGACUCCACAGCAUAUGGAGGAGCUGGCAGAGCAGGAGAUUGCUAGGCUAGUACUGACAGAUGAGGAGAAGAGUCUAUUGGAGAAGGAGGGGCUUAUUCUGCCUGAGACACUUCCUCUCACUAAGACAGAGGAACAAAUUCUGAAACGUGUGCGGAGGAAGAUUCGAAAUAAAAGAUCUGCUCAAGAGAGCCGCAGGAAAAAGAAGGUGUAUGUUGGGGGUUUAGAGAGCAGGGUCUUGAAAUACACAGCCCAGAAUAUGGAGCUUCAGAACAAAGUACAGCUUCUGGAGGAACAGAAUUUGUCCCUUCUAGAUCAACUGAGGAAACUCCAGGCCAUGGUGAUUGAGAUAUCAAACAAAACCAGCAGCAGCAGCACCUGCAUCUUGGUCCUACUAGUCUCCUUCUGCCUCCUCCUUGUACCUGCUAUGUACUCCUCUGACACAAGGGGGAGCCUGCCAGCUGAGCAUGGAGUGUUGUCCCGCCAGCUUCGUGCCCUCCCCAGUGAGGACCCUUACCAGCUGGAGCUGCCUGCCCUGCAGUCAGAAGUGCCGAAAGACAGCACACACCAGUGGUUGGACGGCUCAGACUGUGUACUCCAGGCCCCUGGCAACACUUCCUGCCUGCUGCAUUACAUGCCUCAGGCUCCCAGUGCAGAGCCUCCCCUGGAGUGGCCAUUCCCUGACCUCUUCUCAGAGCCUCUCUGCCGAGGUCCCAUCCUCCCCCUGCAGGCAAAUCUCACAAGGAAGGGAGGAUGGCUUCCUACUGGUAGCCCCUCUGUCAUUUUGCAGGACAGAUACUCAGGCUAGAUAUGAGGAUAUGUGGGGGGUCUCAGCAGGAGCCUGGGGGGCUCCCCAUCUGUGUCCAAAUAAAAAGCGGUGGGCAAGGGCUGGCCGCAGCUCCUGUGCCCUGUCAGGACGACUGAGGGCUCAAACACACCACACUUAAUGGCUUUCUGGGUCUUUUAUUUGUACCCAUGUGUCUGUCACACCAUGAAUGUACCUGGGGAAAUCAACUGACCUCCCUGAACAUUUCACGCAGUCAGGGAACAGGUGAGGAAAGAAAUAAAUAAGUGAUUCUAA